GGCCAAGAAGGCAGAAGCCUUCCAGCUGUACCAAGAGGCUGCUCAGCUGGACAUGCUGCUAGAGAAGCUGCCCCAGGUGGCAGAGGAGAUCAGUGGUCCCUUGACUUCAGCCAAUAAGAUCACACUGGUGUCCAGCGGCAGUGGGACCAUGGGGGCAGCCAAAGUGACUGGGGAAGUACUGGACAUUCUAACUCGCCUGCCAGAGAGUGUGGAAAGACUCACAGGCGUGAGCAUCUCCCAGGUGAAUCACAAGCCUUUGAGAACAGCCUGAGCCUUCAGCCCUCACAGAUGCCCAGCCUCAUAGCUGAAGUUGCCUGAAUGAUCCUCCUGUUGCAUGUAACCCACUGGCCUCCCUGAGCAUGUCCAUUGACAGUGAGGUCCCACCCCUCAUCUCUCCUUGCCAAAUAGUUUGUGCCUUGUCUUGAAGGGGGUUGCUCCCCUUGCCAACCUCACACUGCUAUGAUUGCCAACUCCAGCGGUCCCAUGUCAGCCUUCUGAUGAUCCCACUCCACCCCACCUCAACUUAUUUAACUUCCUAAUUAAAUCAGACUGUUUGAGCCUGUUGUCUAGAAUAUUUUCCUGACCAAGACUGAGGGAUGGGCUGGAGGUUUUCAACUUUGCUACCCAAAUAAAUUGCUGUAAGUAAGUACUAAUAAAACAGAAGCAACUGGAAAUUAA